GGAAGAUGACGAGGUGGAGGGGGCAGAGGCGGACCUGUCUGGAGAUGGUACUGACUAUGAGCUGAAGCCUCUGCCCAAGGGCGGGAAACGGCAGAAGAAAGUGCCAGUGCAGGAGAUUGAUGAUGACUUUUUCCCAAGUUCUGGGGAAGAAGCUGAAGCUGCUUCUGUAGGAGAAGGAGGAGGAGGAGGUCGGAAAGUGGGAAGAUACCGAGAUGAUGGAGAUGAAGAUUAUUAUAAGCAGCGGUUAAGUCCCAAGAUGCCUCGAACACUAAGUUUACAUGAAAUAACUGACCUUUUAGAGACAGAUGACAGCAUAGAAGCAAGUGCUAUAGUGAUACAACCACCUGAAAAUGCUACAGCACCUGUUUCUGAUGAGGAAUCAGGAGAUGAAGAAGGUGGAACAAUAAAUAAUCUGCCAGGUUCUUUGUUGCACACAGCUGCGUAUCUUAUUCAAGAUGGCUCUGAUGCUGAGUCUGACUCAGAUGAUCCCUCAUACGCACCUAAAGAUGACUCUCCUGAUGAAGUUCCAUCUACGUUUACUGUGCAGCAACCUCCACCAUCAAGGAGGAGGAAAAUGACAAAAAUUCUUUGCAAAUGGAAAAAAGCCGACCUAACUGUACAACCCGUAGCAGGUAGAGUUACAGCACCACCAAACGAUUUCUUCACCGUAAUGAGAACUCCCACAGAAAUUCUUGAACUUUUUCUUGAUGACGAGGUCAUUGAACUCAUUGUCAAGUACUCCAACUUAUAUGCUUGCAGUAAAGGUGUACAUCUUGGCUUGACUAGCUCUGAAUUCAAAUGUUUUCUGGGAAUUAUUUUUCUGAGUGGUUAUGUCUCAGUUCCUAGAAGGCGUAUGUUUUGGGAACAAAGAACAGAUGUGCAUAAUGUACUGGUUAGUGCUGCCAUGAGACGUGACCGGUUUGAAACUAUAUUUUCUAAUUUGCAUGUUGCUGACAAUGCAAAUUUGGAUCCAGUGGACAAAUUUUCCAAAUUGCGACCUCUCAUAAGCAAACUUAAUGAGAGAUGCAUGAAAUUUGUUCCAAAUGAAACAUAUUUCAGCUUUGAUGAAUUCAUGGUUCCUUAUUUUGGUCGUCACGGGUGCAAACAAUUUAUUCGGGGAAAGCCCAUUCGGUUUGGCUAUAAGUUUUGGUGUGGUGCCACCUGUCUGGGCUACAUUUGCUGGUUUCAGCCGUAUCAGGGUAAAAACCCAAAUACUAAACAUGAGGAAUAUGGUGUCGGUGCGUCACUUGUCCUUCAGUUUAGUGAGGCACUUACAGAGGCACACCCUGGACAAUACCAUUUUGUAUUCAAUAACUUUUUCACCAGUAUUGCACUUCUUGAUAAGCUCAGUUCAAUGGGACAUCAGGCAACAGGUACAGUGAGAAAGGAUCACAUUGACAGAGUUCCACUGGAAUCAGAUGUAGCUUUAAAGAAAAAAGAAAGAGGCACAUUUGAUUAUCGAAUUGAUGGCAAAGGCAAUAUUGUCUGCAGAUGGAAUGAUAACAGUGUUGUCACUGUUGCCUCAUCUGGUGCUGGUAUCCAUCCCCUGUGUCUUGUCAGUCGUUACUCCCAGAAACUGAAAAAGAAGAUACAAGUUCAGCAGCCAAACAUGAUCAAAGUGUAUAACCAGUUCAUGGGAGGCGUAGACAGAGCUGAUGAAAACAUUGAUAAGUAUCGGGCAUCAAUCCGUGGAAAGAAAUGGUAUUCAAGCCCUCUUUUGUUCUGUUUCGAACUGGUCUUACAAAAUGCUUGGCAAUUGCAUAAAACAUAUGAUGAGAAACCAGUGGAUUUUCUGGAGUUUCGUCGACGUGUGGUAUGCCAUUAUCUGGAGACCCAUGGUCAUCCUCCAGAACCUGGCCAAAAAGGAAGACCUCAGAAGCGUAACAUUGACUCACGUUAUGAUGGCAUAAAUCAUGUGAUAGUCAAACAGGGAAAGCAAACGCGAUGCGCUGAAUGUCAUAAGAACACAACUUUUCGAUGUGAAAAAUGUGAUGUUGCCUUACAUGUGAAGUGUUCCGUUGAAUAUCACACUGAAUAGCAGGUGUCACCACCUCCUGAGAUAAGAAACAUAGUUUUAUACAUUAUGUACAGUGUAGCAGUGGUUUUGCCUAGUGUUCCAAUUUUGGAACGUCACAUAACAAUGGAACAUAAUAAAUUUUUUUUUCUCUUCAAAUUUUUGUUCCUUGAAUUUUUCUAGGUAACAUAUAUGAAUUUCAUGCAAAAAUUCAAAAAAUUGUAACCUCAGACAUAAAUGGGUUAAAGAUGU